GUUCCGCCGAGGCUCGCUGGGUCGCUGGCGCCGCCGCGCAGCACGGCUCAGACCGAGGCGCACAGGCUCGCAGCUCCGCGGCGCCUAGCGCUCCGGUCCCCGCCGCGACGCGCCACCGUCCCUGCCGGCGCCUCCGCGCGCUUCGAAAUGAGGGUCCUGGGUGGGCGCUGCGGGGCGCUGCUGGCGUGUCUCCUCCUAGUGCUUCCCGUCUCAGAGGCAAACUUUUGUUUAUAUUUUAGAAAUGAUUUUAUAUACAACCGUGCAUGCAUUUCUGUAUUGGUCGGCUUAUCUGGAUGCAAUUUUUUCUAUUCUAUAUGCUUUUUGUCAAAGCAACAGGCUUCACAAGUCCUGGUUAGGAAGCGUCGUGCAAAUUCUUUACUUGAAGAAACCAAACAGGGUAAUCUUGAAAGAGAAUGCAUCGAAGAACUGUGCAAUAAAGAAGAAGCCAGGGAGGUCUUUGAAAAUGACCCGGAAACGGAUUAUUUUUAUCCAAAAUACUUAGUUUGUCUUCGCUCUUUUCAAACUGGGUUAUUCACUGCUGCACGUCAGUCAACUAAUGCUUAUCCUGACCUAAGAAGCUGUGUCAAUGCCAUUCCAGACCAGUGUAGUCCUCUGCCAUGCAAUGAAGAUGGAUAUAUGAGCUGCAAAGAUGGAAAAGCUUCUUUUACUUGCACUUGUAAACCAGGUUGGCAAGGAGAAAAGUGUGAAUUUGACAUAAAUGAAUGCAAAGAUCCCUCAAAUAUAAAUGGAGGUUGCAGUCAAAUUUGUGAUAAUACACCUGGAAGUUACCACUGUUCCUGUAAAAAUGGUUUUGUUAUGCUUUCAAAUAAGAAAGAUUGUAAAGAUGUGGAUGAAUGCUCUUUGAAGCCAAGCAUUUGUGGCACAGCUGUGUGCAAGAACAUCCCAGGAGAUUUUGAAUGUGAAUGCCCCGAAGGCUACAGAUAUAAUCUCAAAUCAAAGUCUUGUGAAGAUAUAGAUGAAUGCUCUGAGAACAUGUGUGCUCAGCUUUGUGUCAAUUACCCUGGAGGUUACACUUGCUAUUGUGAUGGGAAGAAAGGAUUCAAACUUGCCCAAGAUCAGAAGAGUUGUGAGGUUGUUUCAGUGUGCCUUCCCUUGAACCUUGACACAAAGUAUGAAUUACUUUACUUGGCGGAGCAGUUUGCAGGGGUUGUUUUAUAUUUAAAAUUUCGUUUGCCAGAAAUCAGCAGAUUUUCAGCAGAAUUUGAUUUCCGGACAUAUGAUUCAGAAGGCGUGAUACUGUACGCAGAAUCUAUCGAUCACUCAGCGUGGCUCCUGAUUGCACUUCGUGGUGGAAAGAUUGAAGUUCAGCUUAAGAAUGAACAUACAUCCAAAAUCACAACUGGAGGUGAUGUUAUUAAUAAUGGUCUAUGGAAUAUGGUGUCUGUGGAAGAAUUAGAACAUAGUAUUAGCAUUAAAAUAGCUAAAGAAGCUGUGAUGGAUAUAAAUAAACCUGGACCCCUUUUUAAGCCGGAAAAUGGAUUGCUGGAAACCAAAGUAUACUUUGCAGGAUUCCCUCGGAAAGUGGAAAGUGAACUCAUUAAACCGAUUAACCCUCGUCUAGAUGGAUGUAUACGAAGCUGGAAUUUGAUGAAGCAAGGAGCUUCUGGAAUAAAGGAAAUUAUUCAAGAAAAACAAAAUAAGCAUUGCCUGGUUACUGUGGAGAAGGGCUCCUACUAUCCUGGUUCUGGAAUUGCUCAAUUUCACAUAGAUUAUAAUAAUGUAUCCAGUGCUGAGGGUUGGCAUGUAAAUGUGACCUUGAAUAUUCGUCCAUCCACGGGCACUGGUGUUAUGCUUGCCUUGGUUUCUGGUAACAACACAGUGCCCUUUGCUGUGUCCUUGGUGGACUCCACCUCUGAAAAAUCACAGGAUAUUCUGUUAUCUGUUGAAAAUACUGUAAUAUAUCGGAUACAGGCCCUAAGUCUAUGUUCCGAUCAACAAUCUCAUCUGGAAUUUAGAGUCAACAGAAACAAUCUGGAGUUGUCGACACCACUUAAAAUAGAAACCAUCUCCCAUGAAGACCUUCAAAGACAACUUGCCGUCUUGGACAAAGCAAUGAAAGCAAAAGUGGCCACAUACCUGGGUGGCCUUCCAGAUGUUCCAUUCAGUGCCACACCAGUGAAUGCCUUUUAUAAUGGCUGCAUGGAAGUGAAUAUUAAUGGUGUACAGUUGGAUCUGGAUGAAGCCAUUUCUAAACAUAAUGAUAUUAGAGCUCACUCAUGUCCAUCAGUUUGGAAAAAGACAAAGAAUUCUUAAGGCAUCUUUUCUCUGCUUAUAAUACCUUUUCCUUGUGUGUAAUUAUACUUAUGUUUCAAUAACAGCUGAAGGGUUUUAUUUACAAUGUGCAGUCUUUGAUUAUUUUGUGGUCCUUUCCUGGGAUUUUUAAAAGGUCCUUUGUCAAGGAAAAAAAUUCUGUUGUGAUAUAAAUCACAGUAAAGAAAUUCUUACUUCUCUUGCUAUCUAAGAAUAGUGAAAAAUAACAAUUUUAAAUUUGAAUUUUUUUCCUACAAAUGACAGUUUCAAUUUUUGUUUGUAAAACUAAAUUUUAAUUUUAUCAUCAUGAACUAGUGUCUAAAUACCUAUGUUUUUUUCAGAAAGCAAGGAAGUAAACUCAAACAAAAGUGCGUGUAAUUAAAUACUAUUAAUCAUAGGCAGAUACUAUUUUGUUUAUGUUUUUGUUUUUUUCCUGAUGAAGGCAGAAGAGAUGGUGGUCUAUUAAAUAUGAAUUGAAUGGAGGGUCCUAAUGCCUUAUUUCAAAACAAUUCCUCAGGGGGAACAGCUUUGGCUUCAUCUUUCUCUUGUGUGGCUUCACAUUUAAACCAGUAUCUUUAUUGAAUUAGAAAACAAGUGGGACAUAUUUUCCUGAGAGCAGCACAGGAAUCUUCUUCUUGGCAGCUGCAGUCUGUCAGGAUGAGAUAUCAGAUUAGGUUGGAUAGGUGGGGAAAUCUGAAGUGGGUACAUUUUUUAAAUUUUGCUGUGUGGGUCACACAAGGUCUACAUUACAAAAGACAGAAUUCAGGGAUGGAAAGGAGAAUGAACAAAUGUGGGAGUUCAUAGUUUUCCUUGAAUCCAACUUUUAAUUACCAGAGUAAGUUGCCAAAAUGUGAUUGUUGAAGUACAAAAGGAACUAUGAAAACCAGAACAAAUUUUAACAAAAGGACAACCACAGAGGGAUAUAGUGAAUAUCGUAUCAUUGUAAUCAAAGAAGUAAGGAGGUAAGAUUGCCACGUGCCUGCUGGUACUGUGAUGCAUUUCAAGUGGCAGUUUUAUCACGUUUGAAUCUACCAUUCAUAGCCAGAUGUGUAUCAGAUGUUUCACUGACAGUUUUUAACAAUAAAUUCUUUUCACUGUAUUUUAUAUCACUUAUAAUAAAUCGGUGUAUAAUUUUAAAAUGCAUGUGAAUAUCUUUAUUAUAUCAACUGUUUGAAUAAAACAAAAUUACAUAAUAGA